GAUUGCAUUUGCGGCCUCGCUGCCGUAUCCCAGGCUAAGCGCCGCGCGCAAAGCCGUGCGGAGAUUGGAGGCCGCGCGGGUCCCUGGUCUGGGCCAUGUCUGGCUGUGAUGCUCGGGAGGGAGACUGUUGUUCCCGGAGAUGCGGCGCGCAGCUCUGAAAUUAAAUCCCUACUGACUGGCCCUUGAACUGAUUUUUUCUAACAUCAGCAAAAGUCAAGGAGUGUUUCCCUAAAAAAGAAAGCAUUUACUCAGAAACCGUAUAUUGAAGUCCAGGCUGAAAAAUGCAAACAUGAGACAAGGAGCAUCCAAGAUACCUGAUCCCAGAACUUUGCAAACAGUUUUACCAUUUAGGCUGGGUCACUGGGACUGGAGGAGGAAUUAGCUUGAAGCAUGGCGAUGAAAUCUACAUUGCUCCUUCAGGAGUGCAAAAGGAACGAAUUCAGCCUGAAGACAUGUUUGUUUGUGAUAUAAAUGAAAAGGACAUAAGUGGACCUUCGCCAUCGAAGAAGCUAAAAAAAAGCCAGUGUACUCCUCUUUUCAUGAAUGCUUACACAAUGAGAGGAGCAGGUGCAGUGAUUCAUACCCACUCUAAAGCUGCUGUGAUGGCCACACUUCUCUUUCCAGGACGGGAGUUUAAAAUUACACAUCAAGAGAUGAUAAAAGGAAUAAAGAAAUGUACUUCCGGAGGGUAUUAUAGAUAUGAUGAUAUGUUAGUGGUACCCAUUAUUGAGAAUACACCUGAGGAGAAAGACCUCAAAGAUAGAAUGGCUCAUGCAAUGAAUGAAUACCCAGACUCCUGUGCAGUACUGGUCAGACGUCAUGGAGUAUAUGUGUGGGGGGAAACAUGGGAGAAGGCCAAAACCAUGUGUGAGUGUUAUGACUAUUUAUUUGAUAUUGCCGUAUCAAUGAAGAAAGUAGGACUUGAUCCUUCACAGCUCCCAGUUGGAGAAAAUGGAAUUGUCUAAGCCAAAAGAAAGUCUAAUUAUAUACAGAGAUAAAGCUAAACGUAAUUAUUAUUUAAAUGAAAGCUAUUUUUUUAAAUGAAUUGAAAUUUUUCAUGAUGCUACUAAUUUGCCACUAAAUACUGCAAAUGGUCACCCUGAAUCUCUUCUGACAUUGGAUGUUAUUUGCUUAUAUUCUUAUAAUUUUAAAUGAGGGCACAGUGAAAUGAAAAUUUUAUACUCUAUGUUUCUGUUUAUUUUUAAAUCCUUAACAGCAAAAUAUUUGCCUUUAAUUUCUUUUUUAUAUAUACUCUCAGAGAAUUCCUCUUAAUUUUUAAAGAUGCUGGUGAUAAUAAAAUUCAUUAGAAAAUUUCCUCAUUGUGGAAUGAGCAUUCUCUUGUUUUAAUGUUGGUGUCAGAAAAUAAAUAUGAAACAUUAAGUCCAAA